AUUGUUAAGACAAAGGGUGUGCACUUCCUGGCCAGGAAACCUGAGCGGUGAGACUCCCAGCUGCCUACAUCAAGGCCCCAGGACAUGCAGAACCUUCCUCUAGAACCCGACCCACCACCAUGAGGUCCUGCCUGUGGAGAUGCAGGCACCUGAGCCAAGGCGUCCAGUGGUCCUUGCUUCUGGCUGUCCUGGUCUUCUUUCUCUUCGCCUUGCCCUCUUUUAUUAAGGAGCCUCAAACAAAGCCUUCCAGGCAUCAACGCACAGAGAACAUUAAAGAAAGGUCUCUACAGUCCCUGGCAAAGCCUAAGUCCCAGGCACCCACAAGGGCAAGGAGGACAACCAUCUAUGCAGAGCCAGUGCCAGAGAACAAUGCCCUCAACACACAAACCCAGCCCAAGGCCCACACCACCGGAGACAGAGGAAAGGAGGCCAACCAGGCACCGCCGGAGGAGCAGGACAAGGUGCCCCACACAGCACAGAGGGCAGCAUGGAAGAGCCCAGAAAAAGAGAAAACCAUGGUGAACACACUGUCACCCAGAGGGCAAGAUGCAGGGAUGGCCUCUGGCAGGACAGAGGCACAAUCAUGGAAGAGCCAGGACACAAAGACGACCCAAGGAAAUGGGGGCCAGACCAGGAAGCUGACGGCCUCCAGGACGGUGUCAGAGAAGCACCAGGGCAAAGCGGCAACCACAGCCAAGACGCUCAUUCCCAAAAGUCAGCACAGAAUGCUGGCUCCCACAGGAGCAGUGUCAACAAGGACGAGACAGAAAGGAGUGACCACAGCAGUCAUCCCACCUAAGGAGAAGAAACCUCAGGCCACCCCACCCCCUGCCCCUUUCCAGAGCCCCACGACGCAGAGAAACCAAAGACUGAAGGCCGCCAACUUCAAAUCUGAGCCUCGGUGGGAUUUUGAGGAAAAAUACAGCUUCGAAAUAGGAGGCCUUCAGACGACUUGCCCUGACUCUGUGAAGAUCAAAGCCUCCAAGUCGCUGUGGCUCCAGAAACUCUUUCUGCCCAACCUCACUCUCUUCCUGGACUCCAGACACUUCAACCAGAGUGAGUGGGACCGCCUGGAACACUUUGCACCACCCUUUGGCUUCAUGGAGCUCAACUACUCCUUGGUGCAGAAGGUCGUGACACGCUUCCCUCCAGUGCCCCAGCAGCAGCUGCUCCUGGCCAGCCUCCCCGCUGGGAGCCUCCGGUGCAUCACCUGUGCCGUGGUGGGCAACGGGGGCAUCCUGAACAACUCCCACAUGGGCCAGGAGAUAGACAGUCACGACUACGUGUUCCGAUUGAGCGGAGCUCUCAUUAAAGGCUACGAACAGGAUGUGGGGACUCGGACAUCCUUCUACGGCUUUACCGCCUUCUCCCUGACCCAGUCACUCCUUAUAUUGGGCAAUCGGGGUUUCAAGAACGUGCCUCUUGGGAAGGACGUCCGCUACUUGCACUUCCUGGAAGGCACCCGGGACUAUGAGUGGCUGGAAGCACUGCUUAUGAAUCAGACGGUGAUGUCAAAAAACCUUUUCUGGUUCAGGCACAGACCCCAGGAAGCUUUUCGGGAAGCCCUGCACAUGGACAGGUACCUGUUGCUGCACCCAGACUUUCUCCGAUACAUGAAGAACAGGUUUCUGAGGUCUAAGACCCUGGAUGGUGCCCACUGGAGGAUAUACCGCCCCACCACUGGGGCCCUCCUGCUGCUCACUGCCCUUCAGCUCUGUGACCAGAUGGUUUGUACAAUAAAGGGGAAGAUUAAAGAAUCUCUCUGAAACAUGACAGACAAGUUGGCAAAUUCAUGUCAUGCCAGCCUGCCCCCACACCCGCAUUCUCCUCAGCCCUCCUAGCUGUAUCUGCUUCUUCUCUACAAACAUAAGAAGAAAUAGAAGUCUAGAGGGAAUAAUAAUAGCCUGAUACCCCAUACUGAUAGCCUGAUGAAACCACCUGCUUAUUGUCUGACCUGCUUUUCAUCUGUGAACACAUAAAAAUGUGGCUCUGUUCAUUAACAUUAAGGACAUAGAACGGGGAAACCUUGGCUGCUAAAAUCAAAGGCCAUGACAAGUUUGCUGUUUGAAGUCACAUCAGUGAGAAUGGAACAAGCCACUCUUGCCUGGAAGAUGGAACAUCCCAGUCUUGCCUCAGCAGCAUGCGGGUCCCUUGACCCAGAGAAACAGCCCCAAUCCCAACCCAGGUGCAGAGCUUCAGAUAACCAGAAUGAGCACAACAUUCUACAUUUUUCUUAACUAUGUCAAACAGACAGGACCUUGAGUCAAUUUUGAGGGCCAGGCCUUCAACUCCAGUCUGAAGUUAUUCAUCCAGCAAAUUUUUUUUCUUUCUUUUUUUUUUUUUUGAGACAGAGUCUUGCUCUGUUGCCCAGGCUGGAGUGCAGUGGCGUGAUCGCAGCUCACUGCAGCCUUGACCUCUUGGGCUCAGGUGACCCUCUCACCUCAGCCUCCCGAGCAACUGUGAUCACAGGUGCAUGUCACCACACCUGAUAAUUUUUAAAAACUUUUUGUAGAGACAGGCUCUCACUAUAUUUGUUUUAAACCUAUCAAAGAACUGCUUCAUUUACAUUUUACCCCCAUUCCAUCCUUCCCCAAAUCCUAUAACCACAUGUCCCUUCUUUUGCAUGGGGAGGUGGCCCACAGUGCCUUGAAUGGGAGCCAGUAACUCCCCUGCUAGAAUAAGCUAAUAAACCUAAUUUGUGGACAUAU